AGGGCCACGGCGCGCUCUCCGUGAGACUGUGGAACCGAGGGGGAGUGGGGGAGGGGUGGGCGCUGCAAAUACCAAGCUAGUCCUCCCGGAUCCUCCCCGAUCCUCCCGAGCGCAGUGAUCGUGGAGCAGCAUGUGGGAGUAGGGAGCUGGGCUCUGCGCGCCCCGUCUGGAAACCGUGGGGACUUGCGCCGUUAUUCCCAGCCCUCAAGACGGCCACAAGAAAAGUUCCUCCACACCCACAGACGUGCAAGCGAACACUUGCAGCUGGCAGCCAGUGCACACGCAGAAACGACAUUUCAGGACCCAGCACAGUCUCAUUUGGCUGGAGCCACCGGCUCUGCGGAGCUGACUUGCCCAUUCCCUCUACACCUCACUGUGUCCUUCACCCUGUCUGACCUAGUCCCGGGAAACCUGGUGACUCCCAAAAGCAUCUUCUGCUGCCAGUAACAUAGGUCGAGGCUGGGAGUCGGGAGACUUGAGUUCUAGUUUACAGGCUGUGUAAACCCGGGCAGUCAUCCCUCAGCUCUGCGCCUUGUGCUCGCUUUUCCUGGGCCACCAUUUGUAAAACGGGCCUCCUGCUCCUGUUGCCUGCAUACCCCAUGGGACAGAAGGGGAAAGGGGGAUUGGACCUCAGAGUCUCUUAUCUCGAAAAUAAAUGAGUUUAGUUCUUGCGUGAAAGCCCACCAGAGUAUCCCUCCUAAAAUCCUCUCCACUAAUUUGCAUAUAGGGAAACUGAUGCCCCAGGGGAGAUGAUUUACCUAAGGUUACAACAGAGACCAAACAGAAUUAGAACCCAAGUUUCCUCAGUCCUAGCCCAGGGCUCUCUCCACUUCACCUACAAAGGCAUGUUGUAAACGUGUGAGCUCCUCCUUAUUUCCUUGCAUCCGUCCACUUUGUCUGUUCCUGAUGGAGGAAGACCCAUGCUGGGGGCCUAGAAGCUGCUUUCAGAUUUUCUUGACUCCUUGAGAUGAUAACCAUCACCUUCUCCAUCCCUCACUCAGUCUAUACGUCUCAAAGCACAUCCAUAAACUUAAUGUGCGAGUGCUCAAAAUACCUUCUAAGAGGGAAGCAAGACAAGAAACUCCAUCUUACUGAUGAGGAAAAUGAGGCCUAGAGGGAUAUAGACUUAGAGUGAUAAAGUUACUUAACCAAAACGCACGGCUAGACGUGUUGGCCUAGUAGGGGCAGGAACCCAGGUCUCCUGAUUCCCCCUCUGAUGUGUUCUCCACCAGCUACAGGACUACAGAAUGGUACCCCUCAAUGAUAAGGGACUGCGGGAAUGAUCAUAGAGGGUAGGAAACAGGAAGGCUUCUGGAGAAGGUGAGGUUCCUGGGAAUCAAGAAGAAUAAUAAGAACCUCCUGGCUGCUUCUGAGGCUAGGAGACCUGGAGUGGGAAAGGAGACACAGAGAUGGUUGUUCUUGGUAAUAUGGGGGGAAAGGAAAGAUGUGGAGACAGAAAAGGAAAACAGUGUGACCAGCCUGCCUGAUAAUUAUCUUGUAUGUUUGCAAUUUCUAAAACAUUCCCAUCUCUUGUCUCCUCUAGUUCUCAUGUGUGGUAGGCAGGGCAGGGAUCAUUAUCCCCAUCUUAUAGAUGAGGUUCAGAGGAAGUAAAUGCAGUGCUCAAGGACACAGAGCCAAGCAUACAGCCAAGAUUAGAAUCAUGAAAGGAACACUUGAACGGCAAGAUCACAGGCUGAGGGACUGGGGAGUUGGACUGUGUGUGUGUGUGCAGUGGGUGGGUGUAUGUGGCCACACCCUGGGUAGGUACACAGGGAAGAGGGUUGCAAAGCCAUUGCUGGUGUUUUGAGGCCAAGAAUGUUUGCCCUUUGGAUUGAAUGGGGUCCAGGUGCAGGGAGCAUCUGGGCUUCCAAAGAAGGCUUAGAAUUCUUCCUCCUCUGACUCACCCCACCUGACUGAGAUGGCUUCUUUUCUUUGAGCCAUCCCUUCCCCAGACCAAAUGAAAUCUGUUUUGCCCUGCCCUGGAGGUUGCUUUUUAAAUAUUGUAAACUGUUUUCAUGAAUGUAUGUGCGUGUGCCAGAGCGGGGGAAUGCUCUUAGAGAAGAGGCAUUGAUUCAUUUAUUCUUGAAUGCCUGCUAGGUAUCAGGGCUGGGAAAUAAAGAAAUGUAUGAGGCACAGGACCCUGCCCUCUUACCUUAAAGCGCACAGUUACACACAUACACAUACACACACACACAUACACACACACACACACACACACAGAGUUUCAGUACAGUAUAGUGCUCUAAUAAGCCUUCGUGCAAAGCACUUUUGGGAAAAAACAAGAGGGAGAGACUAACUGGCUAGGGAGUGAGGAAGGAGGAGUCCCAGGAGAAGGUCUGCAGAGAUGAAUUGGAGUUGGGUCUUGAAGGAUGAGUAGGAGUUUGCCAGGCAGGUAAAAAGAGGAAGGGCAUUCUUGUUUAAGAAAACAGCAUGAGCAAAGGCAAGAGAUGUGCAAGUGCAAGGAAUAUUUGGAGAGUGGCCUGUACUUCAGUGUCAUGGGUGCAGGCCACUGAAAAGAGCUGUGGGGAGAUGAGGCCAGUGUCAGAGUCACAUUUCAAGGAGCUUCAGUGGUAAUCAGAAGAGUUUAGAGUCUGCCCUACUGGCAGAAGGGAACUUAUAGUGGAAAGGUCUGUGGAGGGGAAGUCAAGAUACUUGGUUUCUGGCUCCAACUCUGCCACUACUGAGCUGUGAGACCUUAAGCAGGUGAUUCCCUUGGGGAGGAGGGUCUAUUUUCCCACUGGUUGAAUGAGGGGGUUGCACCAACAACAUGAUCAUGAAGAUCUCUUCCAGCUCAGAUUCUAUUCCUUUGUCCUUCCAACUGGAUGCUAAGGGCUACUCCUUCAACUCCUCUCCCACUCCACCAGCUCUCCAAUCCACAGGAGUGGUAAGACCACCAAGGGGACAGUGGUAAAACUGUGCACCCCAGGAACUGUCUUUGGAUCACCUACCUGCUUUAUGUGACUUUUUCUACCUACCUCUCUGUACUUCAUUUCCAGACACUGAAGACGCUCAUUCUGAAAGAGUAGCUGAAACGGAGUGACGGGAAAGAAAGACCCAAGGCUCUGGGCUUUCCCAGCUCCGAAGUCAAUACUGAGAUCCCAGAUGUGUCCAGAGACAUCCUGAAGAGGCUCGGGGGUGGAGGAGCCUUAGUGUGUCCACAAAGGGACUCCUGAAACUGACUGAGAGCCAGUGGAUUUGCCAGCAGUCUGAGCUUCUACCGAGUCUUCCCCCACCUCAAUCCCUGUUGCUAUGGAGACUACCAAUGGAACGGAGACCUGGUAUGAGAGCCUGCAUGCCGUGCUGAAGGCUCUAAAUGCCACUCUUCACAGCAAUUUGCUCUGCCGGCCAGGGCCAGGGCUGGGGCCAGACAACCAGACUGAAGAGAGGCGGGCCAGCCUACCUGGCCGUGAUGACAACUCCUACAUGUACAUUCUCUUUGUCAUGUUUCUAUUUGCUGUAACUGUGGGCAGCCUCAUCCUGGGAUACACCCGCUCCCGCAAAGUGGACAAGCGUAGUGACCCCUAUCAUGUGUAUAUCAAGAACCGUGUGUCUAUGAUCUAACACGAGAGGGCUGGGACGGUGGAAGACCAAGACACCUGGGGAUUGCGUCUGGGGCCUCCAGAACUCUGCUGUGGACUGCAUCAGGUCUCAGUGUCCCUAUCUGUAAGAUCAACAAGAAACACGGUUAAGGGAGGUCGUCACUGGGGUGGGAGAAGAGGGGCUGGUAGACCGAAGCCUUGUGCAUAAGGAUUUUUUCCCAGGAAAAGAUAGACUUUAUAAACAGUGGGAGCCCAUGAACAAACAUAUAAAAGUAGCAACAGAUAAUGACCAAUAACUGGUUCAGUGGCUGGAGUAUUAGGGGCCUGGGGAUUGGAGAACGGAGAAGAAGUUGUAGCAGAGGGAAAUGAGACAGGAAGAUGCUCUGGGGACACAUUUUUUAUGUGUUAUCUUCAGCCAUGAGAAGCAGUGAUGACUAUCCCAUAUCACAGAUAUGAUUUACCACCACCACCCUGCCCCCGCUCCCGUGAAGAAAGCAGGGCAAGUGCUGUGCUGCCCAUUUGGGCCUGCAUAGUGCCAUGAUUGGAACCCAGGAACUCUGGUCUCCUUGCCUAGUGCUUUUCAAAACUCUGUGCUACACAGGAGUGGAUCCAGGCCUGAAGGUCAUACAAUUCUGGGGACUCUCUUUAAGAAAAAGAAUUCUAAAAUAUCUUACUUUUGCAAACAUUAUGAAAAUAUACUGCCACAUUAAUAUGUUGCUAGGGCCCCUGCUAGGACCUUAAGAAGGAGCUCAUGUGAGUCAGGACCCUGAAUGUUAGGCCUCGUUAGCUCUAUGGUUCAUAUGCUUCUUGAACCAAGUCACAGGGCACUUCCCAGCCACAUUGCCAGGCAACAGGACUAAACUACCUCCAAAGCAAGCAGUCUUUUCAGUUUUGACUGAGUGAUGUGAGAAACUUCUUUUCUUUUCUUUUCUUUUUUUUUUUUUGAGACAGUCUCCCUAUGUCACCCAGGCUGUGGUGCAGCAACCCAAUCUUGGCUCACUGCAACCCCCACCUCCCGGGUUCAAGCAAUUAUCCUGCCUCAGCCACCUGAGUAGCUGGGAUUACAGGUUCCUGUCACCACACCCAGUUAAUUUAUAUAUAUAUAUAUAUAUAUAUAUUUAAGUAGAGACAGGGUUUCACAUGUUGCCCAGGCUGGUCUCGAACUCCUGUCCUCAAGUUAUCUGCCCAUUUUGGUCUCCCAAAGUGCUGGGAUUACAAGUGUAAGCCACCACGACUAUCUGAGAGAAGUUUUCUGAUGUCAUGUUGAAUCUGCUUCUAAAAGACUGAUACUGCCAAGGUGGGCGGAUCACCUGAGGUCAGGAGUUCGAGACCAGCCUGGCCAACAUGGUGAAACCCCAUCUACUAAAAAAAUACAAAAAUUAGCCAGACCUGGUGGCGGGUGCCCGUAUUCCCAGCUACUUGGGAGGCUGAGGCAGGAGAAUUGUUUGAACCCGGGAGGUGGAGGUUGCAGUAAGCCAAGAUCACGCCACUGCACUCCAGCCUGGGUGACAGAGCAAGGCUCUGUCUCAAAAAAAAACAAAAACAAAAACAAAAAAGACUGAUAUCGCACCUAAAUUAUUAUUAUAUUAAAAGAAGCAGAGUAUGAGAGACAGGUACAUGGUCCAGUAGGAAGAGAAGCAGCCCUGAUUCUACCACUUAAGGUGAUGUAUGAUCUUAGGCUGGACACUUCUCUCCCUCAUCCGUUUUCCUCUUCAACAUAAUGAAAUAGACUUGAAAGUCUCUAAGGCUCUAUCAGUUCUGACAUUCUAGGCUUCAUAUACAUUAAGUUGAGCCAUAUGUAAUCACUGUGUUUGUAGGUUAGAAACAGCUGAGUAUCGUAGUUUCAUAUAUGGUUCCAGCUAAUACAUGCAAUGUGGCUGGUGAACACUUCUGAAUUCAGAAACUAUCCCAGAUCUCAGCUAGAACCAUCCACUGUUCUGUUUGUCCAGUUUCAACUUAAGGGAUCUCCAUGCGGUCCCUGGAAGUACCCAUUGAAACAUGCGUAUUUGUGUAUAGCAGAACUCUGAAAUAAUAUUCUGACAGCAGUUAUCUCUGAGGAAUUGGGUUAUAGGUGAUUUUCCCUUUCCGCAUGAUAAAUUUAUGUAAUAUUUGACUGACUUGACCGUAAGUAUGUUACUUGUAUAAUAAAAGGAAAAAAGGUACUUCUAUUUUGAAAAAAUAAAAAUAAAAGCCUUUGGGUUCUUGAAUGGAGGAUCAUGGAACACAUUUGCUGCCAUAUGCAGUUAUGUUGAUGCUCUGCAAACCUGUGCUGAGCCCUGUUGCUCAAGCCCUUCCUCAUCUCUUCUUGAGGGAGAAGGUGGAGACUUCCUUAAGGAGAUGUGACAUAUGGGAAGACAACAGAUUCAGAAAUUUACGUGGAUAGGACUUUAGACACCACCCAGCCCAAACUUCCAAAUAAAAUAUGGAACGCAA